AGUGAGGCGCCCAGCGGAACGGCCUCUGGUGACAUUUUCUUGGGGGCGGCGCGGACGACUGAAGGGACUUGGUGGUAGAGGCUGCGGAGGCGGCGAGGUUCACUUUGGUCCCGGCAGGGGCUCUGACCGCGACCCACUGCUCGCUGCCGGGGCUUGUUCCGAGGAGGAGAAGGCGGCGGUGGCCGUCGCGUCCUGAGUCACCGCAGCGGGGAAGAGUCCCGGCCGGGGGUUCGGUGCGUGCCCCGACGGGGCGCGCGCGAAGCGAGCGAGAAGGCACGGAGUCGCCGCGGAGCGCAGGUUGCUUUCCUGUUGCAUCUUUGAUAUCAUUUCCUAGACUCUACUCCAUGAUUUAACUUGAAAUUCUGAAAUGAAGAUGGAGGAGGCAGUGGGAAAAGUUGAAGAACUCAUUGAGUCCGAAGCCCCACCAAAAGCAUCUGAACAAGAGACAGCCAAGGAGGAAGAUGGAUCUGUAGAACUGGAAUCUCAAGUUCAGAAAGAUGGUGUAGCGGAUUCUACAGUUAUUUCUUCAAUGCCCUGCUUGUUGAUGGAACUGAGAAGGGACUCUUCUGAGUCUCAGUUAGCAUCCACAGAGAGUGACAAGCCUACAACUGGCCGAGUUUAUGAGAGUGACUCCUCUAAUCACUGCAUGCUUUCCCCUUCCUCUAGUGGUCACCUGGCUGAUUCAGAUACGUUGUCUUCCGCAGAAGAGAAUGAACCCUCUCAGGCAGAAACGGCGGUAGAAGGAGACCCUUCAGGAGUGUCUGGUGCCACAGUUGGGCGCAAGUCUAGGCGGUCCCGAUCUGAAAGUGAAACUUCCACUAUGGCUGCCAAGAAAAACCGGCAAUCCAGUGAUAAACAGAAUGGCCGAGUCGCCAAGGUUAAAGGUCAUCGGAGCCAAAAGCACAAGGAGAGGAUCAGGCUACUGAGGCAGAAACGGGAGGCUGCUGCAAGGAAGAAAUAUAACCUGCUGCAGGACAGUAGUACCAGUGAUAGUGACCUGACUUGUGACUCAAGCACGAGCUCAUCAGAUGAUGAUGAAGAGGUUUCAGGGAGCAGCAAGACAAUCACUGCAGAGAUACCAGAUGGACCUCCAGUUGUAGCUCAUUAUGAUAUGUCUGACACCAACUCUGACCCAGAAGUGGUAAAUGUGGACAAUUUAUUGGCGGCUGCAGUAGUUCAAGAGCACAGUAAUUCUGUAGGCGGCCAGGACACAGGAGCUACCUGGAGGACCAGCGGGCUUCUAGAGGAGCUGAAUGCAGAGGCAGGUCAUUUGGAUCCAGGAUUCCUAGCAAGUGACAAAACAUCUGCUGGCAAUGCGCCACUCAAUGAAGAAAUUAACAUUGCGUCUUCAGAUAGUGAAGUAGAGAUUGUGGGAGUUCAGGAACAUGCAAGGUGUGUUCAUCCUCGAGGUGGUGUGAUUCAGAGUGUUUCUUCAUGGAAGCAUGGCUCGGGCACGCAGUAUGUUAGCACCAGGCAAACACAGUCAUGGACUGCUGUGACUCCCCAGCAGACUUGGGCUUCACCAGCAGAAGUUGUUGACCUUACCUUGGAUGAGGAUAGCAGGCGUAAAUACCUACUGUAAUACAAUGUCACUGUGUUUCCUCUGCACUGUUCCCUUCCACUUCCUCAUCCUCUUUGUGACAUGGAAGUUCAUUGUCAUAGCUUCAGCUUCAGAAGCUGUUUGUGGCAUUUGUAGGAUUCAAACUCAUGGAAAAUUCCCUCCUCUUCCCCCCUUUUUUUAAUUAAAAGAAGUCACUUAGGAAAAUAACAUCACAGAGAAAAGAAUUUCUUCUUUCCCUCAGUAGGAAUAUAGAAUGAUGAAUUUUAUUAGACAACUUUAUUUUACUUGGUGACUUUUAAUCUUAGGAAACUCUGCCUUCCUUUUAGAAUAAUAUUUUAAUUGCCAGGCAAAAUGGGUUUCAGUUUUUGAAUCUUGUAUUUAUUUUUCUGUAUAAUGAAAUUAAUAUCUAGACUUGACCACUAUCUGCCCACCCCAUUGGCACUCCCAUCUUAGGGCAUUCGCACACAUAUCAGUCAGGUCCUUAUUGGCACCUAGUAGGGCAUGUGCAUUUAAAAACUUGUCCUUAAAAAUAGAAGACAGAAGUAUUAAAAUUAUAUUUUCUUUUAUUUUAAGUCUUCUGCCUUCUUUCUUGAGUUUGCUCCUGUUGACUUCCCACAGCACAGAUAAUUGACAUGUCCCUUUGUGUUUAUAAAUACUACUAAGGUGACCUAGUUGUUCUCCUUGUUGCAAUAAUUAAUAACUCUUUGCAAAAUGUCUCCUUUGAGACAGAGGCAUUUCAGAUAGAUACCCACCAUGAGGUGUUCUGGGCAUCUGAAGGUAUUAAGAGUUCAGUGGGAAAAAUCUCUCUCCCUCGCCUUUUUUUCUGGUUUAGUCAAAUAACGGGUGAACAUAGAAACCUGUUGGGAAGAAUAUGAAAAGUUAUGUGGCCUCUGAGGCUACAGGCACUUGCAAAUCCGAGAGGAAAGUGCCGUCUUUCAUAGCUGGUCUCUGUAUAAAGAGUAUGUAGCAACAACUGUUUAACAUCCGAGAUGAAGUGGACCUGAUGCUGUAUUUGGGUAUUUUUCUCCUCUACCUUCUAAAAAAAAAUACCAUAAGAAGAAUCAGAAUGUACCAUAAGAAAUCAGAUGCAAAGCACGUUAAUGUCAUUGGUAAGUUUUACAGAGUCUAAAAGGAUUAGCAAAGGGUAGCAGGAGCUUCAGGGAAUUCAGGAAAUGCCAGCAUUGGAAUUUUGUGGCAUUAGUUACUACCUUCUUUCUUAUAAUAUGUUGUAGUUACUAGUGAAUUCUUUUAAAAGCAAUACCUAGAGUUAGAACACUAUGUACUCUGCACAGGGGGAGUGAAGUAAUAUUGGCUUAGAAGACUUCACCUUUUGUUUUUCAUGGUUUUUGUUUGUUUUGUUUUUGUUUUUGUUUCCAUUGUUACCGUUGCUAUGGCCCUUUGCCUGUCUCUCCAAAUCCCCUGGUGGCUCUUCUUAUCAUUAAGAGUAUGAGAAUUACCAUUUUCAGUUUUCAUUCAGCAAACAAAUUUACCAAGUGCCUGCUCUGCAUAAGGCACUGUGAGGGGUGGGUGCUCUGGGGGCUGCUGAGAUGAAUGACACACACCGCACAUACACAUGCAUCAGUGUCUGCCUGCCUCCACCUGCCCAGCCUGUUCUUCUUCUUCUUCUUCAUCUUCUUCUUUUUUUUUUUUUUUUGUAAAGACAAGUUUAUUCCUUUACGCUUCUUGUUGCAUUAGUUCUCCUGUAUGUUCCUUCUUCCACAGGAAUGUAUUUGUGCAUAUGUUCUUUGAUCUUCUCUGAUAGCAUCUCAUUUGAUCUGGCCUCUGUCCUUCAUCAGCUUUUAUUUUUUUUAUUUUUAUUUUCUGCUUUUGUUAGAUAAGGCUUUUAAGAUCAUGAACCUCCAGCUUUAGCAACUCAUAUAUCAGUCUCUCACAUGGCCACAAUUCUAGACAAAAACCAAAGACCCAGAGGCCAGAGCAAAGUAGGACCUUCUGAAGAUUCACUACUGGUGUAUCCUUGGACCUUCACAUUUUACUUUAGGAUUAAUUUAUUGAAUUUUACUGUUACACAUAGUUUUUGACUUGAAUUAAAAUACUAGACAAAGCAGAAAUGUACAAUUUCUGGUCUGUGUUUUCCAGGAAAUUCAUAGAGAAGAGAAUAGAGUGGAUGAUGUGACUUGAAGUUUUUGCAGCUUAUUUUUUCCCCCACUGUCAGGGCAGAGGCCCAUUUUAAUGAAUGUUUUUGCAUGACCUGUUCUUAUGUUAACCACAUAUUUUUUUUCCCAAUUCCACACAGCAGGUGAUUUCCCGUGUGACAUAUUUUCUUCAUAGUCCCUAAUAUAGUCAUCCUCUACAGAGUUGGCGUGCUGUGUGCACUGUGGAUUAGGAACAGAGUGGAGCUGUAACCAGUCUCUUCUCUGGCCCUUUGCCUUUAUGUCAGCUUGCACUUUUGCCUCACUUAUUCCUAGUCCAGCUCCCAACUGCCUGACUUAAUGGACCAGAACGGAGAUUUGGAUAUUAAGAUGCAGAGGGGGAGGGGAAGGGAUGGUAGAGAUAGACAGCUCUCCCCUACUAGGUUGGGUCAUUUCCCCUAAUAACUAUAGAGAGACUGUGUUUCAACUCUCUUUUCAUUGCUGUUUCCAGAAGAGUGGAGAGUGUGGUUUCAGGCAAGGUAUUAAUGAUACAAUUCCGUGGUAUACAGCUCCUGUGACAUUUGAAGUUUCUUUUAAAGGGGUUUUUCUUAAUCAAAGUUUUACAUUUGGUAGCAUAAGUAGUUCUUUAUGCUUCACAGGACAUUGUCUUCAGAGUAAUCUCUCUGCUAAAAUGGUACAUGUGGGUCACAGAUUGGUUUAUGCCACUGACUUGGUUAAGUUUCCACCCCCUCCAAUUUGUGAAAAACAGAGCAGUGACCUAGCUGUUGCAUCAUCAUGACUGCCAUGUAACCUGUAAUUGCUGCUCUCCAGUAAUUGUCUUUUCAUUUUGAUGGUAGGGGCCAGACUGAAUGAAUAAUGCAUUCUUUUUUAUUCAAUUUAUUUCAUUCAGUUUAUUCUUGGCAAUCAAACAUCCCAUAAACUUUGCUUUUAUUAUCAAUUAUGAAUAUGAAUUGUCUGGUUUACUAAUGUAGUCAUUUGUUCAUCUUUACUUUUAGCAGAUUAGCACCAUAACUAACUUAAAACUAAGUUUGUUACCUGCUUUUUAUACUGUCACAAAGGUUUUUGAAAAAGCUGGGGACACUAUUUUGUCUUUUAGUUUUAAACUUUUUUAAGGCAAAGCAAGCUCCCCAAUCCCUGUUCUCCAAUAUGUGUAUGAUGUGACUUCCAUGUAGAUAUAAAAAUGAUUGUGCCCUAACCAAACUUCCUCAGAUUGUGCACUGUUUGUUUAAAAUAAUCACGUAUUUUAGUCUGAUGCUGUUGUAUUUUUUCAUUUUAUUUAAAACACUACUUACUUCUUAUUCUCUUAACAAAUUUUAAAAGGUAGUGAUCUUAAAAAAAAAUCACUGGAUAACUAGGAAAUAUUUUUGUUGUUGUUUUGUUUCUUAAAGAGUACAGAGGCCAUUGAAGCCUUUUGCUCCUCUUACCGUGAAAAUGAAAUGUUAGCCAUUGUAUGGCUAGGAACCAAUGCACUUGGCAGUUAAUGGAUCUGCUGUUGCUGGAGUGUGAGCGUGGACUUGAUGCAGUGAUGACAAAUCAUUGCUUAGAAUUAAUGUUUUCAAAUGUGCAACUCUAGUUUUUAAAACAAAAUUUGGUUCUUUACAUUCAUUAUUUCGUUUUUGUUUCCCUUUAGUAUUUAAUGGUCUUUGGAGAAAAAAUAAUAAAACAGAGUGUUAUAUAUAUAUUUUUUGGUGCAAGAUAAGAUUUUCUGUUUUUUGAAAUAAGUCUGUAGCAUAAAGGUUAAACUAUUUUAAGACAAAAUAAAAUAGAGUGUAUUUAAACAAUGA